UCUCUGUUAUCACAAAUGCAUUUGUCAUAGCGAUAACAUCUGACUUUAUCCCUCGCUUGGUGUAUGCUUAUAAGUAUGGACCUUGUGCAGGCCAAGGAGAAGCUGGGCAAAAGUGCAUGGUUGGCUAUGUGAAUGCCAGCUUGUCUGUAUUUCGAAUUUCUGACUUUGAGAACCGAUCUGAGCCUGAAUCUGAUGGCAGUGAGUUCUCGGGGACUCCUCUUAAGUACUGCAGAUACCGGGACUACCGUGACCCGCCUCAUUCACUGGUGCCCUAUGGCUACACACUGCAGUUUUGGCAUGUCCUAGCUGCUCGAUUAGCUUUUAUCAUUGUCUUUGAGCACCUCGUGUUUUGUAUAAAGCACCUCAUUUCAUAUCUGAUCCCAGACCUCCCAAAAGACCUAAGGGAUCGAAUGAGAAGAGAGAAGUACUUGAUUCAGGAGAUGAUGUAUGAAGCAGAACUGGAACGUCUCCAGAAGGAACGAAAGGAGAGGAAGAAGAAUGGAAAAGCACACCACAACGAGUGGCCGUGACCAUGUAGAAAAUAGUCCCUUUCCAGGCCAAGGACCUGAAUUCUGUUUACUUCUUCUGGCUGUGCAAAAGCACACUCAAGUGAAUGACUAAAAAUGCAACCACAGUGCAUGUUGCAGAUACCGGCGGCCGCAGGAGGGGCAGCAUCCAGUAGAGGACUGGCGUUGGAGUCACACUGCUGUGAAAUCACGUUGCAGUCCAGCGCACAAUUGCUAUCUAUCCAUAGACCAUUCUUGACCAAGCAAGCAUGCACAUUAUGGGCAGUUACAUUCUCAAGUUUUUAAAAUCAAGGGGAACUUGUAUACUGGGCCUGUUUUUCAGCCUGUUUGCUACCUUUUUUGCAUUCUAUCCCAUGUGAAUUUUACAGACACUGGGCUAAAAAGGGUAUUCAGACACAUGGACACACAUUCCUAGAAUGUCAUCAUAUGGUCCUAAUUCCAUGUCACCAACAACACAGACAAGACCCUGUUUACAACUUUUUCUUUCCUUUUUUUUAAUUUUAGACCUUUCUGAGAAGAUUAUUAUAUAUGACAUAUCUAUAGCUAUGUGUAUGGCCAUAGAUGUAUUUCUGUGUGUACAUAUGUAUAGUCAUGUAUUCCUGCAUAUGUACAUACAAAUACAGAGAUAUAUAAAGUACAUAGAAAUUCCUUACUUGUAAAUAGCCAAAAAGUACUGACAUGAGUGAAUUUUCACAUUUAAAUAGUCAUCAAUAUGAAGCCAUGAUUAAUGCUUGUAUAAUGUGAUGCAAUAAAAUUUAAAAUAAAUUUCUGCACAUGGAAUAUUUUCAGCUG